CCUUUUCCUCCCUGUCGCCACCGAGGUCGCACGCGUGAGACUUCUCCGCCGCCUCCGCCGCAGACGCCGCCGCGAUGCGCUACGUCGCCUCCUACCUGCUGGCUGCCCUAGGGGGCAACUCCUCCCCCAGCGCCAAGGACAUCAAGAAGAUCUUGGACAGCGUGGGUAUCGAGGCGGACGACGACCGGCUCAACAAGGUUAUCAGUGAGCUGAAUGGAAAAAACAUUGAAGACGUCAUUGCCCAGGGUAUUGGCAAGCUUGCCAGUGUACCUGCUGGUGGGGCUGUAGCCGUCUCUGCUGCCCCAGGCUCUGCAGCCCCUGCUGCUGGUUCUGCCCCUGCUGCAGCAGAGGAGAAGAAAGAUGAGAAGAAGGAGGAGUCUGAAGAGUCAGAUGAUGACAUGGGAUUUGGCCUUUUUGAUUAAAUUCCUGCUCCCCUGCAAAUAAAGCCUUUUUACACAUCUC